UCUCAAGAUAUAUGAGAAGUUUUUCAGUAACUUUCAAGCUACUUAUAUUUGUUCCCCCACCCAUAUAGUUAUGACCUGCAGUAAAACUUCUGAAACAAAUAUUUUCCUUUAAAGGCACCAAGAAUCAUGGUCUUAUCACCAUGACAAGAGGGUCCUAACUUUCAUUUUUGAUGUAGGGAAAUUAACUUAGUUUUUAUUCUUAUUCAGAAGUUCUACAAAGUCAUGUGGGUUUCAGCUGAACACAGGAUGUGGGCACAGAACCCAGGGUUGCUUGAGGGUUAGAUGAGACUUGGGAGGGUGUUGGGUUUUGCCUACCAGGAGCAGCUAUGUUUUUGUUUUUGUUGUUGUUGAUUUGUUUUUACUCCUGAGCUUCUGGACCAGUUUGCCAUUAGAGCAGCCAAGAAGAUGUAAGACUGUGUAUCUCAUGCAAAAGUGUUUUUACCAUGAAGAUCUGACUUCCAAAUUCACAGGGGUCUCUCAUCAGUCAGAGCUGAGUAGCUGACUUAAGCUCACAUGACCCGGUGAAGGGCAAGCAUCAUCAGGUGGACUUGAGGGCUUCAAGUACGCUGCCCUGAAGCGCCAGGAAUGUGGUUGCUAGGCAUCCUCCCCAGGAUCUACCCAGGACUUUCCUAUCCAAUUUUGUUGAAGCAAAACCUAGGGAUUAAAUUAAAUGCAACCUCACAAACUACCAAUGAAGGGUGUGGAAAACAGGGAUCCUCUUUUUAACUAUCUGCCCCCAAAUAUCAAUCCCAAUAAACUGUACUAAAAGCCAUGGAUGGCUAAAAAUGCAGUUUAUGUCUUUUCUCCAUUCAAGCGUUUUUUUAAUCAUUAAACUAUGUUCUCAUAUUUCCAUCAGGCCCCAAUGGAUGGAGGAUGCUAGCCCUUUAAUGGGUGAGCAGGGGAGGAGCUGGGACUUUUAAAGCCAGGAGCGGCAAACAGGUCCUGGCCCAGGCUGCUAUGAAUAACUUAAACAGAAAGGACAGCAACAGUCAGGUGGUUUACCUUCCAGAGGCUGGCAAUGCUGUUUCACUGGAGGACACGGCUAAGAAGGAAGUCCACCAGCCUGCCAAGAUGAAUUGCCUUGAAGGGCCAGGUAAGACCUGUGGCCCCUUGGCUUCUGAGGAGGAGCUGGUGUCUGCCUGCCAGUUGGAAAAAGAAGAAGAGAAUGAAGGGGAGGAGGAGGAAGAGGAGGAGGACGAGGAGGAUCUGGACCCAGAUCUGGACCCAGACCUAGAGGAGGAAGAGAAUGAUCUUGGGGAUCCAGCUGUACUUGGUGCUGUCCACAACACCCAGAGAGCUCUGCUUAGCUCCCCUGGAGUCAAGGCCCCUGGUAUGCUGGGAAUGUCACUUGCCUCCUUGCAUUUUCUGUGGCAGACCUUGGACUACCUGUCGCCCAUCCCUUUCUGGCCUACAUUUCCCAGCACCAGCUCUCCAGCACAGCACUUUGGACCUCGGCUGCCCUCACCAGACCCAACUCUCUUCUGCAGCCUGCUGACCUCGUGGCCCCCUAGGUUCAGUCAUCUGACCCAGCUCCACCCUCGGCACCAACGAAUCUUGCAGCAGCAGCAGCAUAGUCAAACACCAAGAGAGCCCCACUUCCUGCUCACCACACUCCUUAGGAAGUGCCAGUGGUGGGAAUAUUACCAGAAGCUAGAGAAGAAGCAGGCAGACGAAGAGCUACUUGGACGAAGAAACCGGGUUGAGUCCCUCAAGCUGGUAACGCCUUACAUUCCGAAGGCAGAGGCUUAUGAGUCCGUGGUCCGAAUCGAGGGUUCCCUGGGCCAGGUAGCUGUGUCGACAUGCUUCAGCCCUCGCCGAGCUAUUGAUGCGGUACCCCAUGGAACUCAAGAGCAGGAUAUAGAAGCUGCAAGCAGUCAGAGGCUUCGGGUAUUAUACCGGAUUGAGAAGAUGUUCCUUCAGUUACUAGAAAUAGAGGAAGGCUGGAAGUAUAGGCCUCCACCGCCCUGCUUUUCUGAGCAGCAAAGCAACCAGGUUGAGAAGCUCUUCCAGACCUUAAAGACCCAGGAGCAGAACAACCUGGAAGAGGCAGCAGAUGGCUUCCUGCAGGUGCUCUCUGUGAGGAAGGGGAAGGCCCUGGUGGCCCGGCUGCUCCCCUUCCUGCCCCAGGAUCAGGCUGUUACCAUUCUUUUGGCUAUCACCCACCAUCUGCCCCUCCUGGUCCGGAGGGAUGUGGCUGAUCAGGCCCUACAAAUGUUAUUCAAACCUCUGGGCAAAUGUAUUAGUCACUUGACCCUCCACGAACUCCUCCAAGGACUUCAGGGAUUAACGCUGUUGCCACCUGGCUCCUCAGAGCGGCCAGUCACCGUGGUGCUUCAGAAUCAGUUUGGAAUAUCUUUGCUCUAUGCCCUGCUGAGCCAUGGGGAGCAACUGGUAUCGCUGCAUUCUUCCCUAGAGGAACCCAACAGUGACCAUACAGCUUGGACAGACAUGGUGGUUCUGAUUGCCUGGGAGAUAGCCCAAAUGCCUACAGCCUCUCUGGCAGAACCCCUAGCUUUCCCCAGCAACCUACUUCCCCUGUUCUGUCACCACGUGGACAAACAAUUGGUUCAGCAGCUGGAGGCCAGGAUGGAGUUUGCCUGGAUUUACUGAUCUGUUUGUUCUGGAAUACGUGUAUGUGGGAAGUUGAAUCAUCAGACACUAGCUACAUAGACUAUGUUUACAGGGAUCCAGAGAGUCUGAAGACAUUUCUUAUGCCUUUAUAUAUUGGAGAACCCUUCCCCAUUUUCAUAUCCUUUCUUCAAAAAUCUAAAUGAUGUGCCUAAAAAUAAGACAUGGCAUAAUAAGGUAUAAUUAAAGAGAUAAUAGAAUGA